UUCAUGUUUAAUUUCUAAUUCUUUGCACAAAAGUAAUUUUUUGGAAAAGCUGUUUCUUGGUUUCAUUUUAGAAUUCCCAGCAACCAAAAGUAAGCCUGAGUUUGUACCAAGGUAGGAAGUAUUUUAUGUUUUAUCAUGUCUGCUAGUCUUGUUCUAUUAAAUUACUUAAGCAACUUUUUAUUAUAGGAAAUUUGGAAAUGUGAGAUGUUUAGCGCAAGGAAAUGAUCUUAAAUGGAACAAAGCUGGUUAAGAAAUUGAAAUGAAUAAAAAGCAUGUUAUGAAAAUAUGCAACACUCUCAUUGACCUAAUUAAAAUAGCUUAUAUAAGAUUAUUGUUGGACUAUGUCUUAUAAACUUACAAGGGAAAUCUUGAUUCCCUCUCUUUAACUCCUUAUAGUUAUUGCCAAGAUUAAUAUUCUUACAUGUAUAUUUUUACAAAUAUGUAUGAUAGAAUGGUCACUGUAAAAAAGUUCUAUUUUUAAAAACAUUGGCAUGAGAAAAAGGUGAAUGCUUCUUAAUAAAGUAUUGGAAUAAUUAUUUAUUAGUGUUACUGGAAAUGGGUGAUUCAGUGUCACUUUUUGGGUAAUGUGGAUUUGUUUUGAGAGAGAAACAGAGAAACAAGGAAACAAAAAUCAACAAAGACUAACAAAAUUUCUGCCCAGAAUACAGGUACGUGCUUGCAUGAAACAAAGGUCCUAUCAUGAAAAUACUAAAAGUCUUUGAAGAACUAGGCUGGAGUUUAUACUGUUAGUGUUCUUUAUUGACGAUAUAUGGAACAUACAGUUAUAUAUGUGAUGAAGUUAACAUUAAUGAUAUAAAUUUCCCAGAUGUAGGGCUAACACUUCUUCAAAAAUCAGAUUUCCAGGUAUUUCAUAGCUUGAACAAAUAUUUGAUGAGACCCCUCCCCUGAAAUUUUAUACCCUAGAACUUAAUAAACAUGCCUGGAAAUUUUAUGUAGAUGAAGGAUUGGGGUUUCUAGAGGUCAUGGCAUAAGUCAUUCUUUCCUACCUGGCCUUUGUACAAUACCAGAUACAAAAUGAAGAGUAAAGAUAGAGGCCAGAACGUACCUACUAAUGAUAAAAGUCCAAGUGGAGGUCUGAGUUUGAGAGCCAAAUGACCUGCUGAUUGAAUUGCAGAACCAGGCCAACUUUUUCAAGCACUCUUCAGGUAAUAUAAAUAAGACAGUGCCAUAGAGCAGGGAUCUUUAUGGUUUUUGUUGCAAUUGUAGCUACUCUGUGAUUGUGAUGCAAGAAAACAGCCAUAGACAACAGGUAAGCUAAUGAGUGUUCCAAUAAAACUUUAUUUAGAAAAAUAGGCAUCAGCCUUUUGUAGUUUGCUGAUCUCUUGCAUAGAGGAAAAAGACACAUUUGCAUUUUCUGCAGCCUACUAGUUUCAACAGGAAGAAAAGGGGCCCAGCAGAAUCCUGCAUACCAAGGAUUUUUCCUCACCAGUUUUUCACCAGAUUAAAAUACUCCAUCUUACCAGAAUUAGAGGGAGUAAAGGGAGAGAAAGAAACCUGAAAUAAUACUAAUGAGCUCUCCUUGUAAGAAGGGGGGCAAACGCUUUUCUCACAAGUCCCUUGACACUAGAAUUUACUCUGUUACUCAGGUAUACUGCCUUUCCAGUGGACUCAAAAGAACCUAUAAAACACAAAGUAUUACUUUGUACUGCAUUUUCCAAACUUGAGAGUCUAAGUGUUUUGGUGCUAAUUUUGGCGUAGUUUCUCUCAUUUUUUGGUUAGUGAUAGUAAAACCAUGUAAUGAGCUCCCAGGAAGACCCUUCUCUUCCGGCCACAUGUGUUGACAUGAGGACAUGCCUUUGGCCUAUUUUGGGCAGCUAAGAUUACUCUGUGGAUUGAUUCAUAUUUUUUGAGUGCCUACAAAAUAUGAGGCAUUUUGAUAAAUGCUGGGGAUACAAUAAUGAGCAAUAGUGAUCCAGUUCUUACCCUCACAAGAGCUUGUGCUGUGUAACAGAAAGGGCUCUAAAAAGAAAAAGUGAUUUCUAAUUUGAAACCUGAGGGACUAGCAGCACAUGCCAAAGGGGACAAAGUUCAGCAUGUUCCGGGAUUUGGGGAAAGCAUUGUUUAUCUGGGGAACAGAGUGUAAGGGGAAAAUGGAGAUAGAUAGCUGAGGCUGGAAAAGGAGGAGGGAGCCUAGGUUGCAAAACCUGUGUAAGCACUUGGGUUUUGUCAGAUCAGCAGGACGUGGUUGAGGGGCUUUAAAGCCAUAAGAUGAUGUGAAUGAUCUCUGUUUUUGAAUAUGUUCAGUCUAGGUUAGAAGAGGCAAAAAUUGAAGACCUACAUUUGUACUGUUCAACAAAGUAGCCAUGGGCCAAAGUGGCUGUUGAGCACUUGAAAGGAGAAUAUAUAAAAAACUGGAGGCCAAGAUACUUCCUUUUGAAGACAGAUGGCUCAUUCAUAGGAUAUAAAGAGAAACCUCAAGAUGUGGAUUUACCUUAUCCCCUCAACAACUUUUCAGUGGCAAAAUGCCAGUUAAUGAAAACAGAACGACCAAAGCCAAACACAUUUAUAAUCAGAUGUCUCCAGUGGACUACUGUUAUAGAGAGAACAUUUCAUGUAGAUACUCCAGAGGAAAGGGAAGAAUGGACAGAAGCUAUCCAGGCUGUAGCAGACAGACUGCAGAGGCAAGAAGAGGAGAGAAUGAAUUGUAGUCCAACUUCACAAAUUGAUAAUAUAGGAGAGGAAGAGAUGGAUGCCUCUACAACCCAUCAUAAAAGAAAGACAAUGAAUGAUUUUGACUAUUUGAAACUACUAGGUAAAGGCACUUUUGGGAAAGUUAUUUUGGUUCGAGAGAAGGCAAGUGGAAAAUACUAUGCUAUGAAGAUUCUGAAGAAAGAAGUCAUUAUUGCAAAGGAUGAAGUGGCACACACUCUAACUGAAAGCAGAGUAUUAAAGAACACUAGACAUCCCUUUUUAACAUCCUUGAAAUAUUCCUUCCAGACAAAAGACCGUUUGUGUUUUGUGAUGGAAUAUGUUAAUGGGGGCGAGCUGUUUUUCCAUUUGUCGAGAGAGCGGGUGUUCUCUGAGGACCGCACACGUUUCUAUGGUGCAGAAAUUGUCUCUGCCUUGGACUAUCUACAUUCCGGAAAGAUUGUGUACCGUGAUCUCAAGUUGGAGAAUCUAAUGCUGGACAAAGAUGGCCACAUAAAAAUUACAGAUUUUGGACUUUGCAAAGAAGGGAUCACAGAUGCAGCCACCAUGAAGACAUUCUGUGGCACUCCAGAAUAUCUGGCACCAGAGGUGUUAGAAGAUAAUGACUAUGGCCGAGCAGUAGACUGGUGGGGCCUAGGGGUUGUCAUGUAUGAAAUGAUGUGUGGGAGGUUACCUUUCUACAACCAGGACCAUGAGAAACUUUUUGAAUUAAUAUUAAUGGAAGACAUUAAAUUUCCUCGAACACUCUCUUCAGAUGCAAAAUCAUUGCUUUCAGGGCUCUUGAUAAAGGAUCCAAAUAAACGCCUUGGUGGAGGACCAGAUGAUGCAAAAGAAAUUAUGAGACACAGUUUCUUCUCUGGAGUAAACUGGCAAGAUGUAUAUGAUAAAAAGCUUGUACCUCCUUUUAAACCUCAAGUAACAUCUGAGACAGAUACUAGAUAUUUUGAUGAAGAAUUUACAGCUCAGACUAUUACAAUAACACCACCUGAAAAAUAUGAUGAGGAUGGUAUGGACUGCAUGGACAAUGAGAGGCGGCCGCAUUUCCCUCAAUUUUCCUACUCUGCAAGUGGACGAGAAUAAGUCUCUUUCAUUCUGCUACUUCACUGUCAUCUUCAAUUUAUUACUGAAAAUGAUUCCUGGACAUCACCAGUCCUAGCUCUUACACAUAGCAGGGGCACCUUCCGACAUCCCAGACCAGCCAAGGGUCCUCACCCCUCGCCACCUUUCACCCUCAUGAAAACACACAUACACGCAAAUACACUCCAGUUUUUGUUUUUGCAUGAAAUUGUAUCUCAGUCUAAGGUCUCAUGCUGUUGCUGCUACUGUCUUACUAUUAUAGCAACUUUAAGAAGUAAUUUUCCAACCUUUGGAAGUCAUGAGCCCACCAUUGUUCAUUUGUGCACCAAUUAUCAUCUUUUGAUCUUUUAGUUUUUCCCUCAGUGAAGGCUAAAUGAGAUACACUGAUUCUAGGUACAUUUUUUAACUUUCUAGAAGAGAAAAACUAACUAGACUAAGAAGAUUUAGUUUAUAAAUUCAGAACAAGCAAUUGUGGAAGGGUGGUGGCGUGCAUAUGUAAAGCACAUCAGAUCCGUGCGUGAAGUAGGCAUAUAUCACUAAGCUGUGGCUGGAAUUGAUUAGGAAGCAUUUGGUAGAAGGACUGAACAACUGUUGGGAUAUAUAUAUAUAUAUAUAAUUUUUUUUUUUUAAAUUCCUGGUGGAUACUGUAGAAGAAGCCCAUAUCACAUGUGGAUGUCGAGACUUCACGGGCAAUCAUGAGCAAGUGAACACUGUUCUACCAAGAACUGAAGGCAUAUGCACAGUCAAGGUCACUUAAAGGGUCUUAUGAAACAAUUUGAGCCAGAGAGCAUCUUUCCCCUGUGCUUGGAAACCUUUUUUCCUUCUUGACAUUUAUCACCUCUGAUGGCUGAAGAAUGUAGACAGGUAUAAUGAUACUGCUUUUCACCAAAAUUUCUACACCAAGGUAAACAGGUGUUUGCCUUAUUUAAUUUUUUACUUUCAGUUCUACGUGAAUUAGCUUUUUCUCAGAUGUUGAAACUUUGAAUGUCCUUUUAUGAUUUUGUUUAUAUUGCAGUAGUAUUUAUUUUUUAGUGAUGAGAAUUGUAUGUCAUGUUAGCAAACGCAGCUCCAACUUAUAUAAAAUAGACUUACUGCAGUUACUUUUGACCCAUGUGCAAGGAUUGUACACGCUGAUGAGAAUCAUGCACUUUUUCUCCUCUGUUAAAAAAAAUGAUAAGGCUCUGAAAUGGAAUAUAUUGGUUAGAAUUUGGCUUUGGGAGAAGAGAUGCUGCCAUUUAACCCCUUGGUACUGAAAAUGAGAAAAUCCCCAACUAUGCAUGCCAAGGGGUUAAUGAAACAAAUAGCUGUUGACGUUUGCUCAUUUAAGAAUUUGAAACGUUAUGAUGACCUGGCAACAAAAAGUAAUGAAGAAAAUUGAGACCUGAGUGAAGAUAAGAAAUGAUCUUUACGUGGCAAAAUGAACACAUCUUGAGUAUUUAGGAAAUGGGCAGUGAAGGCUAAGAACCUGGUGUGUUUCUUGGGAUCAUGGUACAUUUAUCACUGAAUUAAGCCAUCAGGGAAAAAACAACAAAAAAAGAGAACACCUCCAGCUUUUCUUUUUCUGUAUAUACUCAUGUCCCCCAGAUUCCAACAUUUCUCACUGAAAGGGGGCAUGUAUGCAAACCUCAUCUUUCUCCUUCAUUAAUGAUGAUCUUCAGAUUAAACCCUUUGGUGCUAGGAGCUGACAAUUUCCAAAGCAGCCUGUGAAGUCCUAGGGGCUGGGGGCCACUCUUGCGGCAAGCAGAAGGCCAUCCUACUCCGCGGAGUGAUCAUGGAAAUGUAUUUUAGUUAAACUCUGACAGCUCCCAAACGGAAGACUACAGCAUGACGUAGUAUUAUGAUUGCAUUGUAUGAAAGAGCAAGUGACUUUCUAAGUAGGAUGAAUCAUAUUCAUAUGCAGAUGUCUUAGCCUCUUGACGCUGGAAGUGUGGAUUUAUAGCUAUGAAACCACUGCUGGCAGUGGGUGGGCCACUGGGACUGACGGGGGUUAAAGGGCAUUUUACUAAGGCAGCUAAGACAUAUUCAGACAUCAACGUUAUCCUUCUUUUUCAUAUUUCUACCUGAGUGAAGUUCAUCCUUAGUAUUGAGUAGGAAGUUACAGUAAAUGGUAGUUCAUUCUUACUUACACACAUAGCUAAUCUUUUUUUUUUCACUUGGAAUUAUGUUGAAUGUUUCAUUUUGACAAAAAAGUAGACUAGAAGGUAUGUUCUUUAAGUUGUCUUGCAUCCAUUAUAUAAGAAAGAAACAGGUGAGAGGAAGAGCAGAAAGCUGAGACUGGCUGAUGUUCAGAGCACUUACUCCUCUAGAGGGAAAGCAUGACACCGAACACUAAGCACACAGCUUUUUGUUGUUUUGGUUUUUUCUCCCGCAAAUCUUAAAGUGAUUCCCAUGACCUUGGCCAAGGACACUUCUUAAAGAUUAAUGACUGGCACUGACAUUGCCCCAGGCGGGCCACUCCUCACACUGGCUCUCAGUUCCCAGCCAUGCCUGGGGCUCAGUCACUUCUAUUCCACCCUCUGAGACUCCAUUGGUGUCACACAAGGUGUCUUCUUGGCUUUGAUUUUGAGAAUCCCCUAUUUUCACUUCCAGAUCUGUCAGCUGCCAUGGAGGAAUAAUAGAAAACCAGAAAUGCGUGUAGAGGGAGAUUUCUAAAACUUCCCUUGUGUCGCCCAUAGUUGUAGUUUUGGGUUCUGGCAGGUGGAACACCCUGAAACCUGGAAUCAUUCUAUGAGAAUACAGUUCAGACUUUGCAGACUCCAGCCCAUACUAACUGUCAUGAAGCUUGACUUCUUGUCAUAAUGCAGCCAUCUUGGAGGAAAUUGGCCAUUUCUGCUUAGAUGGUUGGCAGGGUCGCGCUCAGCUUUGCUUUCUACACUAAUUACAUAGCAUUAUUCAAGUAUUGUUUUCCAUUUCCCAUCCCUGAUUUCCAGCUUCUUAAAGCUGACUGUUCUUGCAGGGGCCACUUGCUUCUCCUAGAGUACAAAAGUAAGGGCCUUCCUUACUAACUGCAGGGUCUCUCUAUUACACCUCAACAUACACACUUUGCUGCUACUGUUUGUACUGUCUACAGUAGAAUUUCCUUAUCUUGCUCCUGGUAGUGCAUUACAGGCAAGCAUGAAAUGUAAAGUAUUUAUUUAAAUAAAAAGAAAACCUCUAAAUUGGUAAUUGAAUUACCUCCCUGUAGCUUUAUAGUUUGUGACAUUUCUUGACCUUGCUAGUUCUUUCAUUAGAUCUGCGCAAGAUCUAGUCAUCUGGUUAAGGAUUUUAAGCAGAUGCAACUAUAAACCCAAGAAACUGUAUUACUAUUACUGUUGGUCAUACUAAACCUGUCUAUUUCCUGAAGUAUAUGACCCACAAGGAUGUGGAAUAACUAGGAGAAACUGUUUUUGUACACUGUACAUCCUUAGUAUUUUUACACGUAUAUGAUAGGGAUGAACAUGAUUUUCCUUCGUACAGACAGCUUAAAUAAAGCACUAUGUCAAUCUGCUACUUCUCUGUUUAUUGUUGUUGGAUGUGGUUCUAUAAUCCCCCCAAAUUAAAUCUUCUUUAAUGAAAACAUGAUUUUUAAUAGCCCCAGCUGGUAUUAACCUACCUUGUAUAAAAUGUGACAGGAAAAUAUAGAAAUAAUUCCUUGUAGCUCACACACACACACAUAGGGGAUCAUUUUUACUUCAGUGAAAUGGCAGUAGUGCGGUUGUGCAAACUUUGAUGAACGGCUGCUUCUGAGGGGAAACGCUGACCUCUCAGCACUGGAUUUAGGAUGGAUGUACUGUGAAGCCAGGGAUGAAGGAGGUCUCAGACCCUGGGGACAUUCAGACCCGAAUCAUCUAUACAACACACGGUUUGGACCCAGAAUCUGAAGGAAUGUAGCUUUUCAUUAACGUCUUCCUGAUAAUGUACUGCUCUGCAUAUUUCCUUUCUUAGAGUGUAUUUCUAACAACAUGUCAUGGCAAAUUAACAAACUUAGACGUGGGUGAUGUAGAUGGGUAGGAUGGCUGGACUGCAGUCUGACUUCACGUUGAAUCAUUCUGGAUGGGGCCUUUUUCUGAUUUUACCUCAUAAAGCUACUAUUGUAGAAACUUGGCUUUGCUCCUGUGACGAAGCCAGACAGAGGAAUGGCUUUUGGGACCAGAGUGAGUCAAGCAUGUAUGUGUAUGUCACACGGCCAAAUUUGAGGGCAUUCUCACAUGUGCUCUUCUCUCAAAACCACUGGGGUUGACAGAUCCAGGAGGCUAAAAAAAAGUGACCUCUAUAAUUCUUUAAAGGUGCUAUUUUUAGAAUAUUGUAUAAUUUAUUCACAGUAUAUCUAAAACAGAAUUAAGGACAAUUAAAAUAUCUUAUGUGACAGCCUUUAUGUCUAGCACAUUUGAUGAAAUAAAAAACUUCUGAAUCUGAAUAGAAGUUCUACUGUUUCAGGCUUGAACCUUUUACAUGCUCAAGAGAUUCAAAUGGUCUCUGUGUGUAGAUCAUGCCACCGCCUCCAAAGCCUAAUCCACAUCACUUCUGAGAGGCAAGGCUGAGCAUAUGGUGACAUCAGCUCUGUGUUGAGAUGGUGAUGAGGAUGAUGGCUCGCUGGCCAGGCAGGGCAGCCGAAGGUCAGGGACCUGUCCUAACUAACUGCAGCCUUGCCUUUAGUGUUUGUCAUUCUCAGAUACAACACGGUAUGUCCAGUGUCCGUUUUUAUUACUUUAAAGCAUUUGAGGGCUUAAUUGUGUAUAGUAGAAAUACUAUUUUAGACAAAUAAUUAUCUGUGUACAGAUAUUUGAUAUACUCUAAGUAAAUUUUCUAAUUUCACUAAGUACGUUUUUAGGCUCCUCUCAAAUACUGCGUAUUGAAGAAAAAAAUCUGACACCACCGAGCCAAAGAUGCUUUUUUGUCUGUUUUCGUUGUUUAACAGAAUGGAAAGAGUAAUGCAUAGUGCUUCCUGGUGUCUCCUGAUUGAUUGAUUGUGCACAAAGUAGGACGAUAAAUAAAUAAAAUGGAGUCUGAUGGGACAUUGAUUAAAGGUGAAGGAUGAUUGAUAUAUAGAUCAUGAAAAGAAAAAUGAAUGGCAGGAAAAAAAGUUUGGUCCUUAAUAUACUUUGGCCUAGUUAAAAUAUGUGCCUUUUUGGUGUGUUUUGUUCAUCACUACAAGAUAAAAAGGAAACAUUACAACUCAAGUCUUUAAAAAGUUCAUUUAUUGAAAAUCAUAUGUAUAACCUAGCAUACGAAUGAGCAGAUUUAAACACAUAACUUCAAGCCAUUUCUGAAAACAUACACCAGGAGCUCUGCUCAGCUAGAGUCAGACUCCAGCUCCAGCCCGACUGCGUGCGGGGACAGCGCCCGCGUUGAUGAGGACCAGCCCCACUGCAGGCUGAGGCGGUGUCACCCUGGGAAGGUCGUGGUGCGUUGUGGCAUAUUAAGUCUAAACCAGAUGAAUGUAAAUAUCUCUUUGUAAAUCAUUUAUUUCACUCUGUUCCAUCCAGGUCAGCAAUCAGAUUGUGGCAUGCUGGGUAACUGGAAAAAAUAAUAAAAAGUAAGUUUCAAUA